ACAUUACAUUUAGGAGUGAAUGCACGUCACAUUAAACUGUGUGACACAGUUGUGGGUCGUGGGAUCUCAUUGGCAAUAUUGGGAAGGGCUGUGUGUGGGACCAGUGGAUUUUGCCCCGAUCGAGUCACGCUUUCUUCAGAUAGUUGUUGAAGUUGUUCCACCUGCCCUGUUCCUCAAGGCCCAAUGAAUAAAAACCUGCUCUCCUGCUGUGUUUCUUGCCUAAAGGGAGAUGCUGACUUUCCCUAUCUUGUCUAAACAGGUACCUCCUGUCCUGUGUUUCUAGAUUCCCAGGAACAAUAGGCAAUGUUAAGCUUCCAUUUUAACCCUUUAGGAGCAGUGCCUCCGUGAGUUUCCAGAUGGCUAGGGGACGAUGCGAAGAAACUACAAGGAUGCUGCAGGAUUGUGUUGUGGGCAAAUGGAAACCUUACAGAAACAUGAAGCCCUCAACCAUCUGCUACUCAGUUAUUCGGGGCUGACGGCGGCUUCUAGAACAUCCAGGUGUUCUGCAGAUGCGAGAACUCAUCCUGUAGUCACCAGAUGGAGUCCCAAACAGCCAAGCAGAUGUAAGGCCUGUGCUGUGGCUCUGAGGCCCUGAAUACAGAAGGGUCACUUUCUUAGUGGCCAAAGAGCAGUUGUUGACAUUGAUGUCUAAUUAUUGAACACGACCAGUCAUUUUACUGAGCUGCGGUGAGGAAACACUGACCAUAGAAGAUCAAGCCAAAUGAGGGAUUGCAAAUUUCCUGAUUCUUUUGAAUUAGGAUUCCAGAUGGGGGCCUCAUUUCUACAGCCCCCAACAUUCCUAUAGCCGUUAUCACUGCCAUCACCACUGCCACCAGCAUCUUCUUGCAGAUUCCACCCCUGCUCCCCAGAGACUUCCUGCUUUGAAAGUGAGCAGAAAGGAAGCUCUCAGAAAAAUCUCUAGUGGUGGCUGCCGUCGCUCCAGACAAUCGGAAUCCUGCCUUCACCACCAUGGGCUGGCUUUUUCUAAAGGUUUUGUUGGCGGGAGUGAGUUUCUCAGGAUUUCUUUAUCCUCUUGUGGAUUUUUGCAUCAGUGGGAAAACAAGAGGACAGAAGCCAAACUUUGUGAUUAUUUUGGCCGAUGACAUGGGGUGGGGUGACCUGGGAGCAAACUGGGCAGAAACAAAGGACACUGCCAACCUUGAUAAGAUGGCUUCGGAGGGAAUGAGGUUUGUGGAUUUCCAUGCAGCUGCCUCCACCUGCUCACCCUCCCGGGCUUCCUUGCUCACCGGCCGGCUUGGCCUUCGCAAUGGAGUCACACGCAACUUUGCAGUCACUUCUGUGGGAGGCCUUCCGCUCAACGAGACCACCUUGGCAGAGGUGCUGCAGCAGGCGGGUUACGUCACUGGGAUAAUAGGCAAAUGGCAUCUUGGACACCACGGCUCUUAUCACCCCAACUUCCGUGGUUUUGAUUACUACUUUGGAAUCCCAUAUAGCCAUGAUAUGGGCUGUACUGAUACUCCAGGCUACAACCACCCUCCUUGUCCAGCGUGUCCACAGGGUGAUGGACCAUCAAGGAACCUUCAAAGAGACUGUUACACUGACGUGGCCCUCCCUCUUUAUGAAAACCUCAACAUUGUGGAGCAGCCGGUGAACUUGAGCAGCCUUGCCCAGAAGUAUGCUGAGAAAGCAACCCAGUUCAUCCAGCGUGCAAGCACCAGCGGGAGGCCCUUCCUGCUCUAUGUGGCUCUGGCCCACAUGCACGUGCCCUUACCUGUGACUCAGCUACCAGCAGCGCCACGGGGCAGAAGCCUGUAUGGUGCAGGGCUCUGGGAGAUGGACAGUCUGGUGGGCCAGAUCAAGGACAAAGUUGACCACACAGUGAAGGAAAACACAUUCCUCUGGUUUACAGGAGACAAUGGCCCGUGGGCUCAGAAGUGUGAGCUAGCGGGCAGUGUGGGUCCCUUCACUGGAUUUUGGCAAACUCGUCAAGGGGGAAGUCCAGCCAAGCAGACGACCUGGGAAGGAGGGCACCGGGUCCCAGCACUGGCUUACUGGCCUGGCAGAGUUCCAGUUAAUGUCACCAGCACUGCCUUGUUAAGCGUGCUGGACAUUUUUCCAACUGUGGUAGCCCUGGCCCAGGCCAGCUUACCUCAAGGACGGCGCUUUGAUGGUGUGGACGUCUCCGAGGUGCUCUUUGGCCGGUCACAGCCUGGGCACAGGGAAGAGGAAGCAGGAGGAGGCAAGGAGGCGGAAGGAGCACAGAGUCCCCUCUGCAACGCCCUACAAAUGCAUGGCUUCUUGGUGCUGUUCCACCCCAACAGCGGGGCAGCUGGAGAGUUUGGAGCCCUGCAGACUGUCCGCCUGGAGCGUUACAAGGCCUUCUACAUUACCGGUGGAGCCAGGGCGUGUGAUGGGAGCACGGGGCCUGAGCUGCAGCAUAAGUUUCCUCUGAUUUUCAACCUGGAAGACGAUACCGCAGAAGCUGUGCCCCUAGAAAGAGGUGGUGCGGAGUACCAGGCUGUGCUGCCCGAGGUCAGAAAGGUUCUUGCAGACGUCCUCCAAGACAUUGCCAACGACAACAUCUCCAGCGCAGAUUACACUCAGGACCCUUCAGUAACUCCCUGCUGUAAUCCCUACCAAAUUGCCUGCCGCUGUCAAGCCGCAUAACAGACCAAUUUUUAUUCCACGAGGAGGAGUACCUGGAAAUUAGGCAAGUUUGCUUCCAAAUUUCAUUUUUACCCUCUUUACAAACACACGCUUUAGUUUAGUCUUGGAGUUUAGUUUUGGAGUUAGCCUUGCAUAUCCCUUCUGUAUCCUGUCCCUCCUCCACGCCGACCCGAGAGCAGCUGAGCUGCGCUGGCUCUGGGCAGGGAGUGUGCCUUAAUGGGAAGCACACGGGCUUUGGAGUCAGGCACAGGUGCCAGCUCCAGCUUUUGAACUUGGGCAAUUGUUUAACCUAACCUGCAAGUUGAUUUUGAGGGUUAAAUAAAGGCAUACAUGAAAAUGCCUGGCAAAUUACCUGACACAGAGCAGACAUUCAAUACAUUUUAGUUUCCUUGUUUCUCUGGUUCCCAGUUUCUCUGGUCAUUUUGGUGUAAAUCCAUUCUAAUUAGUAUUUAGGGCAGAGCUUCUCUCUCUUUUCUCUUUUUUUCCUUCCACAAACCAGUGUACUCACUGGUCUCCAUCUUUAAUAUGCAAACAAAUCACCUGGGAUCUUGUGAGAAUCCGGAUUCCGUCUCAGUAGGGCUCGAGUAGAUCCUGAAAUCCUACAUUUCUAUCAAACAAUGCCUUGAGGAGCACAGAUUUAGACCAAAGUUAGGUCGUUUUCCAGAUCUCAGAGCAGACGAGUCCAUGGAUAAGUCUGUGGCCCAAUCCCCUUCCUCUCCUUUUAAGGGUGAAAUGACUGCAUUUAAAAGAAGUUAAAGAGUUCCUCCUGUCCCCUAUAACCACAAGGAAACAAAAAAAUAUAUAAAAACCUCAAAAAUGCAUUGCCAUGAUUUUAUUAUUAGUGUCCAAAAUGGGACUCCCAAGUAAUAAAUGAUUUAUUCCAGCCACAGCCAAAAAAGACUUUGCCUGGCUAAAAGAGUCUCUCUCUAAGUAUGUAAUAUACAAGAAAUACAAUUCAAAGAGAUGUUCCUAUAAGUACAUUUUUUACACGGCAUAUAUUUAAAAAGGAGGCCCCUUUUAAUAUAAAAUUCCGGUUAUAUACCAAUAUGGUUAAUUAGCAUUUACACUAUAGUUUGAACGUAUUUUAAAUAGCAUGAUGUGUAUACAAUGUCUCCCGCGCCCAUUGGCAACCAGGGUCGUGGGAAGCUUGGUGAGGAGUUAACCAGGUCCUGUGGUUUAAGCAGUGGAGCACCCGGGAUUCCUGCCCCCCUUUCUGCUCACACAAUUGCACUCCAUUCUUCCGCCUUCCUUGUUUUCUCCAAAACCACCUGAUAGGGGGGAUGUCCUGAUUUCUGAGGUGUGCUUCUCAUCAUGACUGCUUCGUUUUGCCCUUCUGAUUUCCACGGCACAAGAUUAUCUACCAAAAUCAAAACAGAAUGGCCUUACUCUUCUCAGGAAGAGGCUGGUAGGCAGGUGCAUUAUCAACAGGUCUGUGCCCAUGCAGAGUGAGCAGGGAGAGGCUGGGCACUGUGGAAUUUUUCUGUCUGAACUCGCUCAUGGCCACAGAAUGGUCACCCAGCUUAUUUAGGUGUAGACAAGUAUGACACAGUUCUAGAAAAUACUGACUAUAAAAAUGUCUCUGUGUGUGUGUGUAUGUAUUUAUAUGUAUAUGUAUAUAUUUUUAAAAGGCUCAUCUUACUUGUAAACAUGGACUGCUCAAUCACUAUUAAAAAGUCAGUUUAGGCUGGGCGCGGUGGCUCACGCCUGUAAUCCCAGAACUUUGGGAGGCUGAGGUGGGUGGAUCACUAGGUCAGGAGUUUGAGACCAGCCUGGCCAACAUGGUGAAACCCCAUCGCUACUAAAAAAUACAAAAAUUAGCCGGGCAUGGUGGCGCUCACCUGUAAUCCCAGCUACUCGGGAGGCUGAGGCAGGAGAGAAUCGCUUGAACCGGGGAGGUGGAGGCUGCAGUGAGCCGAGAUCGCACCACUGCACUCCAGCCUGGGCGAUGGAGCAAGACUCCAUCUCAAAAAAAAAAAAGUCAGUUUAGGCUGGGCGCAGUGGCUCACACCUGUAAUCCCAGCACUUUAGGAGGCUGAGGGGGGUGAUCACCUGAGGUCAGGAGUUUGAGACCAGCCUGGCCAACAUGGUGAAAUCCUGUCUCUACUAAAAAUACAAAAUUUAGCUGGGCAUGGUAGCAUGCCUGAAACCCCAGCUACUUGGGAGGCUGAGGCACUAGAAUCACUUGAACCUAGGAGGUGGAGGUUGCAGUGAGUGGAGAUCACGCCAACACAUUCUAGCCUGAGGGACAGAGUGAGACUCUAUCAUCUC